AGAACAGACAGACCUACUGACACAGGGGAGGUGAGAAGGGAGGUGACCACCAGGACUGGUAGGUGGGGAAGACAGGGGGCUUAUGGAUGAGAGCCCGGUGGGAGAUGGGAGGAGAAGAGUGGCUCCUAUGGGGAAUGAUGUGGAGUGUGUCCCUGUCUCUGUCACUCAGUGUAUAUUUCUGCCACUGUGCCGUCCUACCCCUUAACUGUGUAUAGUUUACAUUGUCGAUGUGUCUCACAUACUUUCUGGAUCUUUCAUAUUCAGCAUGGUGUGUAUGCAUAGCUCCUUAUGCGUAUCUUAUAUUGUACAAAAUUGUGCGAGUUUAAUAUUCCCACUGUUUUUAAAGAAACUUUACCCUAUUUACACCCAUUGGUCUGGUGUCACCUUCCUGUCCAAAGCAAGGGACAGAUUAUGGGGACUCACAGAGGCCUUACUACCCUUCCCCCAACCUGGAAGUCCCCCAACUGCUCCGAGCCCUUGCUUUCCCUUAAGACUUCAAAUUUUAGCAAACACAGAAAGUGAAAUCUUGAUCCCCCACAAUAAAAGGGAAAUGAGGAUGGGGUAAGAGACUCUCUCUUCCCCUUACACCUCAUUGUCCUUGGUUUUUUUAUCCGGUUUAGGAAAAAGCCUGGAUUAUGAGGAGGAGAGGAGGAAUUUCCCUGAAGCUCUCUAUUCCCCCACCCCUCAUCCCCUUUCAAUAGGAACUGGGCAUAGGACCAGCUGUGUUGGCAGGGCUUCCAGCAGCUGUGUUAGGGCGAAGGCACUGACAAGUGAGGUUAUAGGGGAGGGGUGCUGCCAGGAUUUCUCUGUCAUACCGUGGGAAGACAAACCCAGCUUAGAUGUCUGGGAUCCCCAUCCAGAGUGGCUGGAAGCUGGGGAAGCAGAAAGGAGACUCUAGUUCUAACUCUAAACAACCUAAUCUUCCCCACUUCCCAUCCUCAACUAGACUUCUAAUCUCCAAGAAAUCCAAUCCAAUGUUCUGCCCCCCUGGCUGGUCUCUUUGUGUCCCUGCUGUGUCCCUGUCCAUCUUACCAUUGUCCAUCCUUUUGUCCCAUGUUGCCCAGGCUCUGUGAGUACCACACAGUGGGGAGGGGGUGGGGGCCACCAUGUCAUCAUAUCAGAAGGAACUGGAGAAAUACAGAGACAUAGAUGAAGAUGAGAUCCUAAGGACCUUGAGCCCCGAGGAGCUAGAGCAGCUGGACUGCGAACUACAGGAGAUGGAUCCUGAGAACAUGCUCCUGCCAGCUGGACUAAGACAACGUGACCAGACAAAGAAGAGCCCAACGGGGCCACUGGACCGAGAGGCCCUUUUGCAGUACUUGGAGCAACAGGCACUAGAAGUCAAAGAGCGUGAUGACUUGGUGCCCUUCACAGGCGAGAAGAAGGGGAAACCCUAUAUUCAGCCCAAGAGGGAAAUCCCAGCAGAGGAGCAGAUCACCCUGGAGCCUGAGCUGGAGGAGGCACUGGCACAUGCCACAGAUGCUGAAAUGUGUGACAUUGCAGCAAUUCUGGACAUGUACACACUGAUGAGUAACAAGCAAUACUAUGAUGCCCUCUGCAGUGGAGAAAUCUGCAACACUGAAGGCAUUAGCAGUGUGGUACAGCCUGACAAGUAUAAGCCAGUGCCGGAUGAACCCCCAAAUCCCACAAACAUUGAGGAGAUACUAAAGAGGGUCCGAAGCAAUGACAAGGAGCUGGAGGAGGUGAACUUGAAUAAUAUACAGGACAUCCCAAUACCCAUGCUAAGUGAGCUGUGUGAGGCAAUGAAGGCAAAUACCUAUGUGCGGAGCUUCAGUCUGGUAGCCACGAGGAGUGGUGACCCCAUUGCCAAUGCAGUGGCUGACAUGUUGCGUGAGAAUCGUAGCCUCCAGAGCCUAAACAUCGAAUCCAACUUCAUUAGCAGCACAGGACUCAUGGCUGUGCUGAAGGCAGUUCGGGAAAAUGCCACACUCACUGAGCUCCGUGUAGACAAUCAGCGCCAGUGGCCUGGUGAUGCAGUGGAGAUGGAGAUGGCCACCGUGCUAGAGCAGUGUCCCUCUAUUGUCCGCUUUGGCUACCACUUUACACAGCAGGGGCCACGAGCUCGGGCAGCCCAGGCCAUGACCCGAAACAAUGAACUACGUCGCCAGCAAAAGAAGAGAUAACACUGCAUUUCCCUUUACCAACUAGCGCUGGGAGCACUGGACACUUAAAUCCUCAUCUGUCCUCCUUUCCUGUAAAUAAAAGCCCUUCUAUCCA